CAUGAAAAAAUAAUGAUGACAAUGCUUUAAUUUCAUUUCUCUGAGCUUUAAUUCUGUAUUAAGGACUGUGCUGUGUUUUAAAUUGAUGAUUUGAUCCCCUCAACAGUCCUGAGGUUAGUCCUAUAGUGACAUGCCUCCAGGUUCCACAUCCCACAACCAGCAUUUGAUAGAGUAAGAAUCCCAGUGCUGUGGAGGAGGUCCUACUCUUCUUGAUCUUUUAAUGCCCCACCUGUCAGUCUCCUGCUGGGCUCUCUGUUGCCUGGGAAGAUUUCUCUGUAGGUGUUCCUGUGAGUUUCCUUAGUGCAGGUUAAUGAUGGUUGUUGAUCACCUGCAGUCCCCAUUGUCACUGAAUGUGAUUGCCUGGAGGUCAUCAGACACUAACUCCUGGGGAGGCACUUAACAUCAGAAGUGUUUAUUAACUUGACCUUGACCAAUUGGCCUCCUUAGAGCUGAGGGGCCAAGAACACUGUCACUGUGUGACAAGGACUAGGAGCCACCCAGACCCAUAGAGUAUUCCCUUCGUUUCAGCAAAUCUGUAUUUUGAGGCUGCCACUGAAGGGUGAAUCAUGGAUGUGGCGUGUCUAGGCAGACUUGGGUGGAGAGGAGUCAGCUCCCUGUUAACAGAGGACUUUGGAGAGGUUUUGAAAGGAAGGGAGAAUGUUGAGGCCUUGUACUGUAUUCCCCUGAUAGCCUGAAUCUGUUGUCAGCUCUUGGACCUUGGAGCAGGUGACUUCACUGGUCCUGCCUCAGUUGCGUCAUUUGUAACAUGGAGGGUUGGAUGCGAUGAGUCCAGUCUUUCCAGCUCUUGACCUUCCAUGUCUGCUGCUGUCUGCAACACUUCCCCUGCCUCUUGCCACCCUUGCUUUUUUUGGCUGUCGUCUCUGUUUUUUUCUUUAUCUUGACUAUUUAUAUUUAUACUUUUCAAGAAGUUAGAGCUAAGAGUGAACGUUACCUCUUUCAUCCCCUUCUUUAAAGAUUCCCUCCUUGGAGAUAUCACUGGAGUUGAUGUGGUGGUUGGUACUUGAGCUGGAAUCCCAAUGGGUGCCUUGCUGGUUUGAGAUUGGGCCGAAUGAGGCCGUGUUGUUUGCCAUCUGUCUUGCCUCAGAGCAGUAUUUUUUGCAGUCUUUGCUGCUUUCGUUGGUCUCUUAAUUAAAACUUUGUUGUGCUUUGCUUCUCUGGUGAAAAGCAGGUUGUGUUAGUGAUGAUCAUGGGGUUUUGUGGUCAUUGAGUAAUGUGGACUGUUGAACUUCAAGAAAAUACUGAUUUUCUUAUAUCCAGCGAGCUUCCUAGAUUUUGUGGGGAACCAGUGUUCUCAUCAUUGGAAGAUGUGCUCUCUAGUGUGAAGCAGUGAUUUUCACAUUUGCCCUGUGAUUCGGUUGUGUUUAUGUUGUGGAGCAGAAAGACCUAGCCAGGGAGUUAGGAGAGCGGGAUUGGAGUUGUAAGGUCAACCUUAUUGUGACCUUGAGCCAGUUAACUGUGUAUCUGGUCUGUAACAUGAGAGAUUUGGACUAGAUGUUCUCUGACCAUCCUCCCUGACCUAAAAAUUCCAUAGUUCUUUGUAUUCAUAUAUACUGGAUGUGAAAAGUCCCUGGAAUAAAUUACAGGAACAAAAAUCAGCCAGGAAUGGCUAGUUGAUAGUCCUGAAAAGACAACAUCAUUGCUGAAUCAUAUCUUCAAGUUGAAUUAUUUAUUUUUGAAAAAACCUUUCUAUAGCAUCCUGAGAAACUUAUUUCUUAUUGUUGUUGCUUUUUUAAAAAAAAAUUGAGAUAGAAUUCACAUACCAUAGAAUUCACUUACCAUAAAAUUCACCAUUUUAAAGUGUCCAACUAAGAGGUUUUUAGUGUACUCACAAAGUUGUGUAGCCAUCACCACUAUUUAAUUCCAGAUCAUUUUCAUCACCAAAAAGAAACCCCAUACCCAUUAGGAGUCAUUCCCUAGUCACCUGUACCCGAGUCCUUGGCAGUCACUCAUCUACUUUCUGUCUCUAUGGAUUUGCCUAUUCUGGUUGUUUCAUAUAUGGAAUCAAACAAUAUGUGGCCUUUUGUGUCUGGCUUCCUUUAUGUAGCCUAAUGUUUUUAAGAUUCAUCCAAAUCAUAACAUGGAUUUGUACUUUAUUUCUUUUUAUGGCUGAAUAAUAUUCUAUCAAAUGUGUAUGAUACAUUUUGUUUAUUCAUUCAUCAGUUGAUGGACAUUUGGGUUGCCUCCACUUUUAGGCUAUUAUGAAUAAUCCUGUGAAUAUUCUUGUAUAAAUUUUUGUGUAGACAUAUGUUUUCACUUCUCUUGGGUAUAUACCUAGGAGUGGAAUUGCUAAGUCACUUUAACUUUUUAAACUUAAACUUUUUAAAGUCAGUUUAACUUUUUGAGGAGCUGCCAAACUGUUUGCCAAAGAGGCUGCACCACUUGACAUUCUUACCAGCCAUGUGUAAGGGUUCUGAUUUCUCCACAUCCUUGACAACACUUGUUAUGUUUGUCUUUUUUAUUACACCCAUCUUAGUGGGUGUGAAGUGGUGGGUUUGAUUUGUGUUUCUCUGAUGGAUGACUAAUGAUUUUGAGUGUUGUUUUAUAUGCCCAUGGCUGUGUGUAUCUUCUUUGGAGAACUAUCUAUUCAAAUCCUUUGCCAUGUUUAUAUUGGAUUAUUUGUCUUUUUAUUGUUGAGUUGUAAUCUGAACAUUAGACCCAGAUCAGAUAUAUAAUUUGCAAGUAAUAAUUUCCAUUUUGUAGAUUGUUUUUUCACUCAUUUGAUGGUGUCCUUCAAAGGACAAAUUUUUUAAUUUUGAUGACAUCCAGAAUAGUCAUUUUUCCUUUGGUUGCAUAAUACAGUCACAAAGAUUUACACCUAUAUUCUGUUUUAUAGUUUCAGUUCUUACAUUUAGGUCUUUGAUCCAUUUUGAGUUAAUAUUUGUAUAUGAUGUGAGGUAGGGGUCCAACUUCAUUCUUUUGCAUAUGGAUAUAUCUAGUUGUCCUGGCACCAUUUCUUGGGAAGACUUUUCUUCUUGAAUUCUCUUGGCAUCCUUUUUAAAAGUUGAUUUACUUCUGAUAUAUGAGUUUAUUUCUGGACCCUCAGUUCUGUUCCAUUGAUCUUUAUGCCUAUCCUUUAUGCUAGUACCAUAAAGCCUUAAUUAACUGUAGGCCUUAUGGUAUGUUUGGAAAUCAGGAAGUGUGAGUCUUUCAACUUUGUUUUUUUUUCCCAAGAUUGUUUUGGCUAUUGAGGCUCCCUUGCAUUUCCAUAUGAAUUUUAGGAUCAACUUUUCAAUUCCUGCAAAAAAGCCAGCUGAGAUUUUCAUUGAGGUUAUGUUGACACUGUAGUUCAAUUUGGGGAGUAUAGACAUCUUAACAAUCUAUCAUAACCUCUUCUAUCUAUGAACUUGGAAGUUUUUUUCAUUUUCUUUUCUUUUCUUUUUUUUUUUUUUUUGAGACGGAAUUUUCCUCUGUUGCCCAGGCUGGAGUGCAAUGGUGCAAUCUUGGCUCACUGCAACAUUGGCCUCCCAAAGUGCUGGGAUUGCAGGCAUGAGCCACUGCACCUGGCCUCAUUUUCUUGUCUUUAAUUUCUUUCAGUAAUGUUUUGUAGUUUUCAAUGUACAAAUCUUACACUUCUUCUGUUAAAUUUAUUCCUAAGUACUUUAUUCUUUUUGAUGUGAGUGGAAUUGUUUUCUUAAUUUCAUUUCUGGAUUAUUCAUUGCUAGUGUAUAGAAAUAUGGUUACUUUUUGUAUAUUGAUCUUAUGGCCUACAAUUUGCUGAAUUUGUUUAUUGGCUUUUAUAGUUUUGUGUAUUUGUAUGUGUAUUCCUUAGGAUUUUUAAUAUGCAAAAUAUCAUCUGCAAAUAGAGACAGUUUUGUUUAUUCUUUAAUAAGCUGAGCACCUUUUAUUUCUUUUUUUUGUUUUUUUGAGACGGAGUCUCGCUCUGUCGCCCAGGCUGGAGUGCAUGGCGCCAUCUCGGCUCACUGCAAGCUCUGCCUCCCAGGUUCACGCCAUUCUCCUGCCUCAGCCUCCCGAGUAGCUGGGACUACAGGUGCCCGCCACCACGCCUGGCUAAUUUUUUUUUUUUUGUAUUUUUAGCAGAGAUGGGGUUUCACCAUGGUCUUGAUCUCCUGAUCUCGUGAUCUGCCCGCCUCGGCCUCCCAAAGUGCUGGGAUUAGAGGCGUGAGCCACCGCGCUGGCCUAUUGCUUUUUCUUAUCUGAUUGCUGGAUCAGUUCUUAAUCAUCUUUAAAUUCCCAAUGAUUUGCACAGAAUAGGUGCUCAGUAACUUUAUUGAUGAACUUCGGUAUUAAAAAUCAGUUUUUAUGUAAGCUGCAGUUUCUUGUAUUUAAUUUGUUUUAUUCUUUAUUUGGCCUCUGGGCAUGUUGAGAAAAUAGGAAGAUUUGCUUGCUUGGUCUUUAGUUGCAAAGGAAGUUAGUGGAAAUGUUUUUGCAUUUGUAAAUGGGUUUUAGAUAUUUGCCUUGUCUGGCCACGGUGCUUGGUAGUCACUCAGGAGGCUUAGAGCCAGGCCUCGUGUGUUCUCUGCAACCGCAAACCCUUUCCAAGCUGCUGUUUCUGCUGGUGAGUGUGGCUGGUGUUUUGGUUGCUUUCUAUCAACAUUGCCUUGAUUUGGUCCCCACAGGAGACUGCUCACUUCUUGACAAAAGGCUUUGGACGUGGACCGGAUGGUUCUUUACAAAAUGAAGAAAUCCGUGAAAGCAAUCAACAGCUCUGGGCUGGCUCACGUGGAAAAUGAAGAGCAGUACACCCAGGCUCUGGAGAAGUUUGGCGGCAACUGUGUAUGCAGAGAUGACCCAGAUUUAGGAAGUGCGUUCCUGAAGUUCUCAGUGUUUACAAAGGAGUUGACAGCACUUUUCAAAAACCUGAUUCAGAAUAUGAACAACAUAAUCUCCUUCCCUUUGGACAGUUUGCUGAAGGGGGACCUGAAAGGAGUGAAAGGGGAUCUGAAAAAGCCUUUUGAUAAAGCUUGGAAGGACUAUGAAACAAAAAUAACCAAGAUAGAAAAGGAGAAAAAGGAACACGCCAAGCUCCAUGGGAUGAUUCGGACUGAAAUAAGCGGAGCGGAAAUUGCCGAAGAGAUGGAAAAGGAGAGGCGCUUCUUCCAGCUACAGAUGUGCGAGUAUCUGCUGAAGGUCAACGAAAUCAAGAUUAAAAAGGGAGUAGAUUUACUUCAGAAUCUGAUCAAAUACUUUCAUGCCCAAUGCAAUUUUUUUCAGGAUGGACUCAAAGCCGUGGAAAGCCUCAAACCUUCCAUUGAAACGCUGUCUACGGAUCUUCACACGAUCAAACAGGCCCAGGAUGAAGAAAGAAGGCAGUUGAUACAGCUUCGAGAUAUUUUGAAAUCCGCAUUGCAGGUUGAACAGAAAGAGUCUAGGAGAGACUCCCAAAUUCGUCAGAGCACAGCUUAUAGCUUACAUCAGCCUCAGGGAAACAAGGAACAUGGGACCGAGCGGAACGGCAGCCUCUACAAGAAGAGUGACGGGAUCCGAAAAGUGUGGCAGAAAAGGAAAUGUUCAGUUAAAAAUGGUUUUCUGACCAUAUCCCAUGGUACCGCUAACCGGCCUCCUGCAAAGCUCAACCUGCUAACCUGCCAGGUGAAGACCAACCCUGAGGAGAAGAAGUGCUUUGACCUCAUUUCACAUGACAGAACUUACCACUUUCAAGCUGAAGAUGAACAGGAAUGUCAAAUAUGGAUGUCUGUGCUGCAAAAUAGCAAAGAAGAAGCUUUAAACAAUGCAUUUAAGGGGGAUGACAAUACUGGAGAAAAUAACAUCGUCCAAGAACUGACAAAGGAGAUCAUCUCAGAAGUGCAGAGGAUGACGGGCAAUGACGUCUGCUGUGACUGUGGGGCGCCAGAUCCUACAUGGCUUUCCACCAACCUGGGCAUCCUGACCUGCAUCGAGUGUUCCGGAAUCCACCGAGAGCUGGGGGUUCAUUAUUCCAGGAUGCAGUCCCUGACCUUAGAUGUACUGGGAACAUCUGAGCUGCUGCUCGCCAAGAAUAUUGGGAAUGCAGGCUUUAAUGAGAUCAUGGAAUGUUGCCUACCAGCUGAGGACUCAGUCAAACCCAACCCAGGCAGCGACAUGAAUGCAAGAAAGGACUACAUCACAGCCAAGUACAUCGAGAGGAGAUACGCAAGGAAGAAGCACGCGGAUAACGCGGCGAAGCUUCACAGUCUUUGCGAGGCCGUCAAAACGAGAGAUAUUUUUGGAUUGCUCCAAGCUUAUGCUGAUGGUGUGGAUCUUACGGAAAAAAUCCCACUGGCCAACGGACAUGAGCCGGAUGAAACGGCCCUCCACCUUGCAGUCAGAUCCGUGGAUCGAACCUCUCUUCACAUUGUAGACUUUUUAGUUCAGAACAGUGGGAACCUGGAUAAACAGACAGGGAAAGGCAGCACAGCCCUGCACUACUGCUGCCUGACCGACAAUGCCGAGUGCCUCAAGUUGCUCCUGCGGGGGAAGGCCUCCAUCGAGAUAGCAAACGAGUCAGGAGAGACUCCGCUGGACAUUGCCAAGCGCCUCAAGCACGAGCACUGUGAGGAGCUGCUGACCCAAGCCUUAUCUGGAAGAUUUAAUUCUCACGUUCACGUUGAAUAUGAAUGGCGACUACUCCACGAAGACCUGGAUGAAAGUGAUGACGACAUGGAUGAGAAAUUGCAGCCCAGUCCCAACCGGCGGGAAGACCGGCCCAUCAGCUUCUACCAGCUGGGCUCCAACCAGCUUCAGUCUAACGCUGUAUCUUUGGCCAGAGAUGCUGCAAACCUUGCCAAGGAGAAGCAGAGGGCUUUCAUGCCCAGCAUCUUGCAGAAUGAGACUUACGGAGCCCUCCUGAGUGGCAGCCCACCUCCCGCCCAGCCUGCAGCCCCCAGCACCACCAGCGCCCCCCCGCUUCCUCCACGGAAUGUUGGCAAAGUUCAGACAGCCUCCUCUGCUAACACCCUGUGGAAGACAAACUCUGUAAGUGUGGACGGUGGAAGCCGGCAGCGAUCUUCGUCAGAUCCGCCAGCUGUCCAUCCACCGCUGCCCCCUCUUCGCGUGACAUCUACCAAUCCCCUGACCCCCACGCCGCCCCCACCCGUUGCCAAGACGCCCAGCGUAAUGGAAGCCUUGAGCCAGCCGAGCAAGCCUGCCCCGCCUGGGAUCUCACAGAUCAGGCCCCCACCUCUGCCCCCACAGCCGCCCAGCCGCCUCCCGCAGAAGAAGCCUGCGCCGGGGGCUGACAAGUCCACCCCACUGACCAACAAAGGCCAACCGAGAGGACCUGUGGAUCUCUCUGCAACGGAAGCUCUGGGUCCUCUGUCCAAUGCUAUGGUCCUGCAGCCCCCUGCACCCAUGCCUAGGAAGUCGCAGGCAACCAAGUUGAAGCCUAAGCGGGUGAAAGCGCUCUAUAACUGUGUGGCUGACAACCCCGAUGAGCUCACCUUCUCCGAGGGGGAUGUGAUCAUCGUGGACGGGGAGGAGGACCAGGAGUGGUGGAUUGGCCACAUUGAUGGAGAUCCUGGUCGCAAAGGCGCAUUCCCGGUGUCAUUUGUGCACUUUAUCGCUGACUGAAUUGCUACUGAACAAAAGCAUUAACAGUUAUGUUCCUGUUUCGUUAUUGGUACCAAAACUCUUGCCAGAUAACCAGUUUCAUGAACUGUUUGUAUGGCAGCCCAUGUUCUCUAAUGCCACUGCUCUGUUUUAAAAACUCAGAGGCAAUUUUUACAUAUCAGUAAUUGUUUUUAUAAUUUGUGGUUUUCAUGAAACAUUGCUAUGCAUUUAUUAGGAAAAACUGAAUUUCCCAACAGGUGAACUGAAAAGUUAUUUUAACUAUUAUACAUAAUCAAGAUCCUGCCUCUACGGAAUUAGCUAAACCUAAAAAUGUUUGCAUUAAUGAAUAAAUUCUUCCUGCAUUCCUUGGCCCAGUUCUGGAGUUGGUGACCUUUAUCACAAUUAUUAUUUUAGGCGGCCAGUGAACUGCUGCUUCAGAAGUCCAUAGCCCAGCUCUGAACUUUCUCGAUAAAAUGCCAUCAGUUCACCUUUAAAGACACACAUUCCUUUGAAAUCCACCCAGUGUUUAAAAAGCAACUUGGAAAUUUACACAUUAGCAUUGUACUUUCUAGCCCUAAUUUGUGAGGUUGCAGCUAUCAUUAUAUUCUGCAUGUAUGUAUAACCUGUUGUGAACAAUCAUACUUAACAAAACUACUGAUGGUUUAUGACAACGUAGGGUAACUACAGUUCAUUCUGUUCCAGGUUAUAUAAAACUGCAUUUCCUGAAUUUGGUUAAAAACUAAGGAUGAUGGAUUGCAAAACAGUUCUUUUAAAUUAGUUUAUAUGCUUUAGGUGUUUUGGAAUUUGCCUUCUUGAACUUCCUGAGUCACACAGAAAGCAACUGUACACAGUAGAAUUCUGUGGCGCAGACCAUGCUGUAUUAACACAUCACUUGCUGUUUCCUACUGAGUGUACCACUGCCUUCCCUUCUAGCCCAGGAGAAUGUUUACUCAGUUUAGUGUCUUGUAUUUCUAUAAUACUCCAACAGGAAUGGUAGUCACACUGUCUUGAAAUUGAAUCUGUCCAUCUGUUUAUAAUCAAGAACAUAUCAGAAAUAUAUAGGUCCCAGGUAAUACUCCCAAACAUCCCACUUUUUACUGUUUCAGGCCAUCAUAUCAUUCUUAAGCUACUUGGGGUGGUAGUAGAGGAUUAGGUUGUCUAUUAUAAAACCAAAACUCAUUCGUUUAAUGAACUUGACUGUCAUACCUCUAUUUAGUAAUUGCGAGGGUAAGAUUCAUAGUAGGAAUAUUGGAAAUUUUGGCACUCUGAGAAUAAAUAGGCAUAUGAUACCCACUUGGACUUUUAACAAAAGUAAAGGAAUAAAUUUGCAUAUAGGCUUGGAAAGUGAGGCAGCAAUGCUGUUAACUGCAUUUGUUGUGAUGGUGCAUUUGAUUGAAGCAGCUUGUCUUUAUUAUGCAAGACUGUGUAGAGUUUUUUUUUUUUUUGGCAUUGUACUUUUUGUUUUUGUUAUAAAGGAAGACAGAACAAACUGGAAUGUUUUAUGAUGUUGUAUAGCAAUCGCUUUUUACCUUUCAAAGUUCCGGGUAAAAAUGUGUUAUAUCUGUAGUUUUUUGUUUUUGUUUUUUUUUAAAGCACUACAUCUGUUUUCACUAAUUGUUAAUUUCUGUUUGAACCCUUCAUUUAAUUUUCUCAUAGAUUUAAGUAAACAGAUGUAUUUUGCACAGUGCACUUAUGUCUAUUUUAACAAUCCUCCUGCAUCUGUAUUUUAUAGUCAGCCUUUUGACCACCUGGUGCCAGCUAUAUAAGGAAUAAAGUUGAUUCAUAUCAACAUUAGAACUCCAGUCCCAAACUAAUCUGUCAGGUUCACUGGUACAUAAAUACCUAGGAAAUAUUUUUCCAGUCUACAAUUUGGUGCUAUUGUGCAGUAACUAAUAGUACUCUUACCAGAGGAGAAAUUAUAUUAACGACCCUGCUAAUAUCCUUUCUUAGUUAUUUGCUCCUUGCAAAUUAAAAAAGCAACUAAGAGAAAGAAAAACAUUGUAGAUAUCUAUUUAUAUUUAAAGUUUAUGUUUCAUGAACUGCAGCUGCAGGAUUCUGGCAUUUUGCAUGCCAUUCUCCAUCAGAUCUGGGAUGAUGGCUCAGAACAUGUACACAGACUAAGAGUAACUGUGUGAUCUGUUAAGGGGUGGAUAACAUAAUAUGCAGCUUAGGAUGCUAUUUUGAGAUGUAUGAUAUUCAGUUCAUUCACCUGAUUACUUUGGUUGCAGCACAACUGUAUAUAUUGUAUAACCGAAAUUGAUUAUUUUCAUUGUCCUUAAUGCAGUGAUUUAUAAUUAGAGCAUGUUUAAUAAGUUUACUCUUCUUGUUAACUAGUCAUUUGACUGGAAAAAAAUAAAAUACUUUUAAAUGGA